CGGGCCCGUGACUUCCCUGGGUUCACGGCAAGGGUGGAACCGGAUUCUGCCCGGAUGGGGAUCUGGAUGGGGGGGUGGGGGUAAGCAUGAAGAUGGUGUUGGUGUAGGGGUAGGGAUUGGGACGGGGAUCCUGAGGCUGUAGAUCCUGGUGGGGUCGGGGGAGUUGGGGGUGGGAGGGGCCUUUGGUCAUCCCUCAAGGUCCUGACUUGGAUGCCAGACUGAGCCUGGACCGCCAUCCUCUGCCGAUUGUGUCUGCUCCCCUCAGACCAAGUCUCUGACUCUGAGUCGGCCCGAAGUGGCAUUGGGGGGAGGGGUGUGCUCGGGGUGAGAUCAUUGCCAGUGUGUACCAGGGCUGACAAGAGGGGCUGAGCUGGAUUCUGUGGUCCCACUAUGUGGGUGAGGGUGGAUCCUCAGUCCUCACUCAGGAGGGUCCUCUUCCUCACUCCUGGCUGUUUGAUGAAGGAAUGGGUGGGAGAUGCUCUGUUUCUGUCACCUCUGAGCAUCUGCGCAUCUGCGCAUCUGCACCCCUUGUAGAGAAUGGCUGCGGGUGCCAGGCCAGGUGCUCCCUGCAGGGCAGGAGCUCCCGCGAUGAUAGUGACCUCUGGGAGAAGACGCACACCUUCCCACGGGGGCUCCUCCCCAGCCAGAGCUACACUUGGCAAACCUUUGGUCCUAAAUGAUUUAUUCUCUGAAUUGAAGAAAUACGGUUUACAUAUCUUCUAAGUAUAUAUGUAGGUAGCAAUAUAUAUAUUUAUUUCUAUGAACUAACACCUACCCUUAGUAUGCAUGAUUCACUCUGAUAUCCUAGUCUACUUCCAUUCCAGUCUUUGUGUUCUGUUGAAAGAAUUUUUUUAAAAAACAUAAUUCCUCUCCCACUCUGUUGGUUUCAGGUUGUUAUUAGCAGAACUCUGGAGCCAUGCUGCCUUAACAAACCCAAUUUUCCUGGUGGACACUGCUAUUACCUAGGGCUCUUGGCAUCGUGUUUUCAGGGGCUGCCUCAGAUUGUGCAAUGAAGUGAAGUGGAAAAUUCAAAACUUUUAUUCUACCCAUUCUUUCAUCUGCCGUCUAGGCAGGCUACAAACCUCCCCAACAUCUCUGCCGCUAACCCCCUCCAACAGACACUGCAAGUGUCACACACAAGUACCAGCUCAACACAGUCUCCAGUCUCACUCUGGGCUUUCCCUGUUUUGUUGUGUAGAUUUUCUUGCUGAUACUGGUGUUUUACUUUCUGUUUCCAUUCUAUAAAUUUACAGGGUUGAUUUGGGAAGCAGAGCACAGCAGCCCAAAUUUGCUUGUAAUGUCGGCGGCUACAGAGGAAAGGCCAAGAAUGGACAGAUUAAUAAAGGGCCAUCUACAAGCCACGAAUAAGGCCAUCACCAGAAGCCAACCCCGCCAGUCCUUGAUCUAGGACUUCCAGACUUCAAAACUGUGAGAAAAAAAAUAAAUUUCUGUUGUUUUAGCUACUCACUCAAUGGCAUUUUGUUAUGGCAGCCUGAGCUGACUUAAGACAUAACUUCAGGUGACACAAUUUUUUUUUUGUUUCCUCCUAGAAAAAAAAAAAGUAAUUUUGACAUUUAAAGUCUGUAGUUCAUUUUGAGUUACAUUUCUGUAUGGUGCAAGAUAUGUGCAAUGGCUAGUACUAUGUGUCAACUUGUCUAGGCUAUACUGCUCAGCUGUGUGGUCAAACAGUAGUCUAGAUGUUGCUGUGAAGGUAUUUUGUAGAUGUGAUCAACAUUUACAAUCAGUUGAUUUUAAGUAAAGCAGUUUAACUUCCAUAAUGUGGAUGGGCCUCAUCCAAUUAGUUGAAGGUGUUAAGAGAAAAGACCAAGGUUUCCUGGAAAAGGAAUUCUACCACAAGACUAACAUAAAAAUGCGCUGUGAGUUUCUAGCCUGCUGGCCUGCCUUCACUGUCCUGGGGGAGGCUUGGAGAGACCAGGUGGACUGGAGUAGACUGUUGAGAGACGCUGGUCUGGUGAAGAUGUCCAGGAAACCACGAGCCUCCAGCCCAUUGUCCAACAACCACCCACCAACACCAAAGAGGCGAGGAAGUGGAAGGCAUCCUCUCAACCCUGGCCCAGAAGCCCUAUCAAAGUUCCCAAGACAACCCGGAAGGGAAAAGGGACCCAUCAAGGAAGUUCCAGGAACAAAAGGCUCUCCCUAAAAGACCGCCGCUUCAAAAAAACCUGAGGAAUGGAGUGGGCCAACACUAUCCAGCCACUCUGACCAGCCGAACGAGGAACUCAAUCAAAAUGAGCCAUAGCGGGACCACAAGGGCAAGGAGACCACCACCUUCUCCAGUCUCUCUUCGGACAGCCAGUAAUUCCCGGGCAAGGCCAGAGACUUCAAGUCUAUCUGAAAAGUCUCCAGAGGUCUAACCCCAGAUAAAUAGCCAACAGGGUGUAGAGUACAUUUUACACCCCAAAGAGUGUGCCCCAUGGUGAUGAAAAUAAAGUGAACAUGUUGCAAAAUGA